AGUUCCUCUACGCCGUCUCCCGCCCACUGGGCGCCUCUGGCUAGCCGGGCUACAGAGUAAGCCUCCAGCAGGGUAGAGUGACAACUCCCCGAUCGGAAGUUACUGUUGAAGCUAAGGCGGCCAUAACUGAUAAUGGCAAAAGGAGAUUCCUGGCUUCCUGUUUCCAGGGUGACGUAGAUUUUUUUCCUUCGCCAGUCUCACCGUUACCCGGGGCAACAGCUGAGCCGUCUGGGAAGGGAUGCAUCUGUAAGUAAGCCCAAAGAGGUACCGUGGGUGACCACACAUCCCAUGUUAGACAAGUUAAUUCAUACUCCGGAUUACACGUCCAGUUUCCUGGCCCUUAUUUUACUGAGACGUCUGGUCACUUACGGAGAUGGACAACAGUUUAGGGCUCCGAAAUUCCCUCUCCUGCCCGGAAGUUGCAUUUGGCACUUCCGAAUUGGGUCAUGGCGGAAGGGUGUUAAUAGCCUGGCCGCCCGUGCCCCAGGGAAUGCUUAUUUUUGACCUUAGUUGCAAAGUGAGUUUCUUCUGUAUGCUUGAGUCAAGAACUCUAAGUCAUCUUGGUAAUACCGGGUUGGAUGCUUAAAGCUGCAGCAAAAAGACCAGAACUUUCAGGAAAAAACACUAUAUCCAACAACUCAGAUAUGGCAGAAGUGAAGUCAAUGUUCCGGGAAGUUCUUCCAAAGCAAGGGCCACUGUUUGUGGAAGAUAUAAUGACAAUGGUGCUGUGUAAACCCAAACUUUUACCCUUAAAAUCUCUGACUCUGGAAAAACUAGAGAAAAUGCAUCAAGCAGCACAGAAUACAAUUCGCCAACAAGAAAUGGCAGAAAAGGAUCAACGGCAAAUAACCCACUGAAUGAUAACUGAGCACUUUAGGGAACAACCUGCCUUAUCUACUAUUUAACAAUAACUAGAAAAUAUGCUUCUGUGUGCUGAAAGUAGUAUGUGUUAUCAAUAAAAUUGAUAGUAUUCAUAGAAAUACAAAAAUAUCCAAGAUUGAUGAAAUUUGUAUUGUGAAUGUAAACACUCUGGUUUGUAUUGAACAUAAACAGUUAAACUAUGAACCAAGUUUUAUGGGGUUUAAGUCAUGUUUUUAGAAUUGCAAAUUAAAUUAUUUGUUCACCAUUCCUAUUGCUAUCUUUUAUAGAUAACAUUCUUGGGAUCUUUUAUAGCAUUCUUGGGCACAAGGGAUUAAAUACAACUUUUAUAUACAGAGGAUCUUUACAUGUUUAUUAAAUCUGAAUUUGAAGAUACAUUCCAAUCUUGCAUAAAGUGUUUGUUGGGCUUUUACAUUACGUAAUUAAAAAACAAAAUUUUUUAACCAAUUUUAUGUGCCAUGUCACGUUUAAUGCUAUCUUGUGUGACCAGAUCCCACCAGUAAUGACAAAACUGUCUUAAACCUCAUUUUUUUUUUUUUUUGAGACAAGAGUUUCACUCUUGUUGCCCAAACGAGAGCAAUGGCACCAUCUCGACUCACUGCAACCUCUGCCUCCCAGGUUCAAGCAAUUCUCCUGCCUCAGCCUCCCAAGUAGCUGGGAUUACACGCAUGCGCCACCAUGCCUGGCUACUUUUGUAUUUUUAAUAGAGACAGGGUUUCUUCAUGUUGGUCAAGCUGGUCAUGAACUCCCAACCUCAAGUGAUCCGCCCACCUCGGCCUCCCAAAGUGCUGGGAUUACAGGCAUGAGCCACCGUGCCCAGCCCUUAAAUCUCAUUUUUAAGAAACCCUCACCUAUUCUGUAGUCAGCUAAGCUUUUAAUUACAUUAAUUUUAAGCACUUGAGAAUAAAAUGACUGCAUUUAUCAUCCAAGUGUCAAACAAUUAAAAACCUAAAAAUGGUAACUAUAUAUAAGCUGAGGUAAUAUGGGCUUGAUAAAGCCCAUGAGGUAAAUAUGAACACUAAACUUGGUUUUAAUUCUAACAGACUAUAUCUAAACCUGUAAGCAGUAUACUCCUAACAGUACCCUCAUAAAUUCUGAAUAUAAUUCUUGUUUGCUGCAGUCAAUAUUUGGCAGUUUAAAUUAGCACAGACGUUGAGGCCUUGCUGAGUUAUUAGGCUAUGUAAAAGAGGUUAAAAAUAUGAUCAUUCUUUAUUGUUAAUUGGUAAUAUUUUCUCAUACAUUAGGUAAAUGUCAAGCUUUGGGUCUCUGGAGUAUAACUUUUUGUAACAUUAGCCAUUAUUUGGUAACAGAAUUUAAGGAUGAUGGAAUGAUGGAAGGUAUUACAUAUUUCUAAAACUUAAUUAAGCUCUAGGUCAGAUAACAAUGGAGUAAAGUGAUACCUGCAUUUUUUUCCCCAGUGUAAUCUUAAUUUACUAUUGUAUUUUUCACUUAAAAUUUUGUAGGGAAAAAAAGUUUUCAAGGGAACACUAAGAUUAAAUUGACUAGGUUCAAAUAUGCUUCCUUAUGAGAUUCAAAAUUUACUGUGUGAAAUUAAAGUUUAAGAGACCUAAAAAAAUGUACUCCCAAUAAAGAAUCAAUACUGCUUCA